GGAUCCGGGCCGCGCUUCCUCUCGCCAGGCCUGCGAGCUUCCUCCCAGCGGAGCCCUGGGCGAGCCGAGGUUGGCCGCCGCCGCCGCCGAGCCCGCUGCCGCCCUCCCGCUCCUGCCCCACCCGCGCCUUGCCCGGGGGCUUCUGCCGGGGUGGGGUCCGAGCCGGGCGACCGCCCGGCUGCGCCGCCGUCGGGGCCGUAACCCGGCCCGCCGUCCCUCCCGCCCCAGCCAGCCUCUGGCCGCCGGAGCCCGCGGGGCGUGGAGCGCGAGGAGCCCCGCGGCCCCGAUCGAGCGUCCGGGGCGGCCCCCGGCAGCCAGCGCGACGUUCCAAAAUCGAACCUCAGUGGCGGCGCUCGGAAGCGGAACUCUGCCGGGGCCGCGCCGGCUACAUUGUUUCCUCCCCCCGACUCCCUCCCGCCCCCUUCCCCCGCCUUUCUUCCCUCCGCGACCCGGGCCGUGCGUCCGUCCCCCUGCCUCUGCCUGGCGGUCCCUCCUCCCCUCUCCUUGCACCCAUACCUCUUUGUACCGCACCCCCUGGGGACCCCUGCGCCCCUCCCCUCCCCCCUGACCGCAUGGACCGUCCCGCAGGCCGCUGAUGCCGCCCGCGGCGAGGUGGCCCGGACCGCAGUGCCCCAAGAGAGAGCUCCCAGUCCACCCUAAACCACAGGCCACAACCAGUGAGGUUCUCACUGGAGCACGGGGAUGUGUGAGAGGCCUUGGAGGCCUCGGCAGCCAACACAGCUGGGGACCCAAGGAAUUCUCCAGAGAGAGCUCUAAUGGUACCAAGUGACAGGUUGGCUUUACUGUGACUCGGGGACGCCAGAGCUCCUGAGAAGAUGUCAGCAAUACAGGCCGCCUGGCCAUCCGGUACAGAAUGUAUUGCCAAGUACAACUUCCACGGCACUGCCGAGCAGGACCUGCCCUUCUGCAAAGGAGACGUGCUCACCAUUGUGGCCGUCACCAAGGACCCCAACUGGUACAAAGCCAAAAACAAGGUGGGCCGUGAGGGCAUCAUCCCAGCCAACUACGUCCAGAAGCGGGAGGGCGUGAAGGCGGGUACCAAACUCAGCCUCAUGCCUUGGUUCCACGGCAAGAUCACACGGGAGCAGGCUGAGCGGCUUCUGUACCCGCCGGAGACAGGCCUGUUCCUGGUGCGGGAGAGCACCAACUACCCCGGAGACUACACGCUGUGCGUGAGCUGCGACGGCAAGGUGGAGCACUACCGCAUCAUGUACCAUGCCAGCAAGCUCAGCAUCGACGAGGAGGUGUACUUUGAGAACCUCAUGCAGCUGGUGGAGCACUACACCUCAGACGCAGAUGGACUCUGUACGCGCCUCAUUAAACCAAAGGUCAUGGAGGGCACAGUGGCGGCCCAGGAUGAGUUCUACCGCAGCGGCUGGGCCCUGAACAUGAAGGAGCUGAAGCUGCUGCAGACCAUCGGGAAGGGGGAGUUCGGAGACGUGAUGCUGGGCGAUUACCGAGGGAACAAAGUCGCCGUCAAGUGCAUUAAGAACGACGCCACUGCCCAGGCCUUCCUGGCUGAAGCCUCAGUCAUGACGCAACUGCGGCAUAGCAACCUGGUGCAGCUCCUGGGCGUGAUCGUGGAGGAGAAGGGCGGGCUCUACAUCGUCACUGAGUACAUGGCCAAGGGGAGCCUUGUGGACUACCUGCGGUCUAGGGGUCGGUCAGUGCUGGGCGGAGACUGUCUCCUCAAGUUCUCGCUAGAUGUCUGCGAGGCCAUGGAAUACCUGGAGGGCAACAAUUUCGUGCAUCGAGACCUGGCUGCCCGCAAUGUGCUGGUGUCUGAGGACAACGUGGCCAAGGUCAGCGACUUUGGUCUCACCAAGGAGGCGUCCAGCACCCAGGACACGGGCAAGCUGCCAGUCAAGUGGACAGCCCCUGAGGCCCUGAGAGAGAAGAAAUUCUCCACUAAGUCUGACGUGUGGAGUUUCGGAAUCCUUCUCUGGGAAAUCUACUCCUUUGGGCGAGUGCCUUAUCCAAGAAUUCCCCUGAAGGACGUCGUCCCUCGGGUGGAGAAGGGCUACAAGAUGGAUGCCCCCGACGGCUGCCCGCCCGCAGUCUAUGAAGUCAUGAAGAACUGCUGGCACCUGGACGCCGCCAUGCGGCCCUCCUUCCUACAGCUCCGAGAGCAGCUUGAGCACAUCAAAACCCACGAGCUGCACCUGUGACGGCUGGCCUCCGCCUGGGUCAUGGGCCUGUGGGGACUGAACCUGGAAGAUCAUGGACCUGGUGCCCCUGCUCACUGGGCCCGAGCCUGAACUGAGCCCCAGCGGGCUGGCGGGCCUUUUUCCUGCGUCCCAGCCUGCACCCCUCCGGCCCCGUCUCUCUUGGACCCACCUGUGGGGCCUGGGGAGCCCACUGAGGGGCCAGGGAGGAAGGAGGCCACGGAGCGGGAGGCAGCGCCCCACCACGUCGGGCUUCCCUGGCCUCCCGCCACUCGCCUUCUUAGAGUUUUAUUCCUUUCCUUUUUUGAGAUUUUUUUUCCGUGUGUUUAUUUUUUAUUAUUUUUCAAGAUAAGGAGAAAGAAAGUACCCAGCAAAUGGGCAUUUUACAAGAAGUACGAAUCUUAUUUUUCCUGUCCUGCCCGUGAGGGUGGGGGGGACCGGGCCCCUCUCUAGGGACCCCUCGCCCCAGCCUCAUUCCCCAUUCUGUGUCCCAUGUCCCGUGUCUCCUCGGUCGCCCCGUGUUUGCGCUUGACCAUGUUGCACUGUUUGCAUGCGCCCGAGGCAGACGUCUGUCAGGGGCUUGGAUUUCGUGUGCCGCUGCCACCCGCCCACCCGCCUUGUGAGAUGGAAUUGUAAUAAACCACGCCAUGAGGACACCGCCGCCCGCCUCGGCGCUUCCUCCACCGA